AAACCUGUCUAAUUGGGGCGGGGAGCGGAGCUUCCUCCUCUGAGGGCCGUGCCGCGCUGCCAGAUUUGUUCUUCCGCCCCUGCCUCCGCGGCUCGGAGGCGAGCGGAAGGUGCCCCGGGGCCGAGGCCCGUGACGGGGCGGGCGGGAGCCCCGGCAGUCCGGGGUCGCCGGCGAGGGCCAUGUCGCUGUUGGGGGACCCGCUACAGGCCCUGCCGCCCUCGGCCGCCCCCACGGGGCCGCUGCUCGCCCCUCCGGCCGGCGCGACCCUCAACCGCCUGCGGGAGCCGCUGCUGCGGAGGCUCAGCGAGCUCCUGGAUCAGGCGCCCGAGGGCCGGGGCUGGAGGAGACUGGCGGAGCUGGCGGGGAGUCGCGGGCGCCUCCGCCUCAGUUGCCUAGACCUGGAGCAGUGUUCUCUUAAGGUACUGGAGCCUGAAGGAAGCCCCAGCCUGUGUCUGCUGAAGUUAAUGGGUGAAAAAGGUUGCACAGUCACAGAAUUGAGUGAUUUCCUGCAGGCUAUGGAACACACUGAAGUUCUUCAGCUUCUCAGCCCCCCAGGAAUAAAGAUUACUGUAAACCCAGAGUCAAAGGCAGUCUUGGCUGGACAGUUUGUGAAACUGUGUUGCCGGGCAACUGGACAUCCUUUUGUUCAAUAUCAGUGGUUCAAAAUGAAUAAAGAGAUUCCAAAUGGAAAUACAUCAGAGCUUAUUUUUAAUGCAGUGCAUGUAAAAGAUGCAGGCUUUUAUGUCUGUCGAGUUAAUAACAAUUUCACCUUUGAAUUCAGCCAGUGGUCACAGCUGGAUGUUUGCGACAUCCCAGAGAGCUUCCAGAGAAGUGUUGAUGGCGUCUCUGAAUCCAAGUUGCAAAUCUGUGUUGAACCAACUUCCCAAAAGCUGAUGCCAGGCAGCACAUUGGUUUUACAGUGUGUUGCUGUUGGAAGCCCUAUUCCUCACUACCAGUGGUUCAAAAAUGAAUUACCAUUAACACAUGAGACCAAAAAGCUAUACAUGGUGCCUUAUGUGGAUUUGGAACACCAAGGAACCUACUGGUGUCAUGUAUAUAAUGAUCGAGACAGUCAAGAUAGCAAGAAGGUAGAAAUCAUCAUAGGAAGAACAGAUGAGGCAGUGGAGUGCACUGAAGAUGAAUUAAAUAAUCUUGGUCAUCCUGAUAAUAAAGAGCAAACAACUGACCAGCCUUUGGCGAAGGACAAGGUUGCCCUUUUGAUAGGAAAUAUGAAUUACCGGGAGCACCCCAAGCUCAAAGCUCCUUUGGUGGAUGUGUACGAAUUGACUAACUUACUGAGACAGCUGGACUUCAAAGUGGUUUCACUGUUGGAUCUUACUGAAUAUGAGAUGCGUAAUGCUGUGGAUGAGUUUUUACUCCUUUUAGACAAGGGAGUAUAUGGGUUAUUAUAUUAUGCAGGACAUGGUUAUGAAAAUUUUGGGAACAGCUUCAUGGUCCCCGUUGAUGCUCCAAAUCCAUAUAGGUCUGAAAAUUGUCUGUGUGUACAAAAUAUACUGAAAUUGAUGCAAGAAAAAGAAACUGGACUUAAUGUGUUCUUAUUGGAUAUGUGUAGGAAAAGAAAUGACUACGAUGAUACCAUUCCAAUCUUGGAUGCACUAAAAGUCACCGCCAAUAUUGUGUUUGGAUAUGCCACGUGUCAAGGAGCAGAAGCUUUUGAAAUCCAGCAUUCUGGAUUGGCAAAUGGAAUCUUUAUGAAAUUUUUAAAAGACAGAUUAUUAGAAGAUAAGAAAAUCACUGUGUUACUGGAUGAAGUUGCAGAAGAUAUGGGUAAGUGUCACCUUACCAAAGGCAAACAGGCUCUAGAGAUUCGAAGUAGUUUAUCUGAGAAGAGAGCACUUACUGAUCCAAUACAGGGAACAGAAUAUUCUGCUGAAUCUCUUGUGCGGAAUCUACAGUGGGCCAAGGCUCAUGAACUUCCAGAAAGUAUGUGUCUUAAGUUUGACUGUGGUGUUCAGAUUCAAUUAGGAUUUGCAGCUGAGUUUUCCAAUGUCAUGAUCAUCUAUACAAGUAUAGUUUACAAACCACCGGAGAUAAUAAUGUGUGAUGCCUACGUUACUGAUUUUCCACUUGAUCUAGAUAUUGAUCCAAAAGAUGCAAAUAAAGGCACACCUGAAGAAACUGGCAGCUACUUGGUAUCAAAGGAUCUUCCCAAGCAUUGCCUCUAUACCAGACUCAGUUCACUGCAAAAAUUAAAGGAACAUCUAGUCUUCACAGUAUGUUUAUCAUAUCAGUACUCAGGAUUGGAAGAUACUGUAGAGGACAAGCAGGAAGUGAAUGUUGGGAAACCUCUCAUUGCUAAAUUAGACAUGCAUCGAGGUUUGGGAAGGAAGACUUGCUUUCAAACUUGUCUUAUGUCUAAUGGUCCUUACCAGAGUUCUGCAGCCACCUCAGGAGGAGCAGGGCAUUAUCACUCAUUGCAAGACCCAUUCCAUGGUGUUUACCAUUCACAUCCUGGUAAUCCAAGUAAUGUUACACCAGCAGAUAGCUGUCAUUGCAGCCGGACUCCAGAUGCAUUUAUUUCAAGUUUCGCUCACCAUGCUUCAUGUCAUUUUAGUAGAAGUAAUGUGCCAGUAGAGACAACUGAUGAAAUACCAUUUAGUUUCUCUGACAGGCUCAGAAUUUCUGAAAAAUGACCUCCUUGUUUUUGAAAGUUAGCAUAAUUUUAGAUGCCUGUGAAAUAGUACUGCACUUACAUAAAGUGAGACAUUGUGAAAAGGCAAAUUUGUAUAUGUAGAGAAAGAAUAGUAGUAACUGUUUCAUAGCAAACUUCAGGACUUUGAGAUGUUGAAAUUACAUUAUUUAAUUACAGACUUCCUCUUUCUAAGAUUUUGUGAAUUGGUUGAAUAGUUCUAUACAAAUGAAGUAUGGAGGUGUGUAUGUUUAUAUGUAUAUAACAAAAUAUUUUCAUUGUGACCACUCUGAAGUAAGAGCAAUGGGAAUGGCAUUAUUGUAGAAUAAGUCAUUGUAUUUUUAACACCAGAAAGAACCUUGCCGAUCACCAGGCAUAACCUAAUUUUAUCCAUGGAAGAAACACAGAAAGGCAUCUAAGUUAGAGCUGGCACCAGAACUGAGACCUCCAGAAAUCUAUUCCAGUAUUUUUUCCACUACACAACUGCCUUCCUGACAGGUUCUGAGAUAAGUGUUAUGUUUGUAGAUAGAGUGAAAUAUAUUUAUAUAUAUAUAAAUAUAUACAGAUACAUAUCUGUGUAUUAUCUCAAGGAAUGUACAAACUUUAGUUUUUGAUUAUAAGGACUUCACUGCAAGUUUUAGUUAAGAGGUUUGUAUAUAAAUCUGUUAUAGAACAGGCUGAAAUUUCUUGUUCAUAAGAUUAUGAAACCACAUGAGAAGUGAUAAAAUGUUUGUUAAAGCUAGAUAGAGGUUAAGAAUCAAGAUAUAAUGGAUAAUUUUCAUAGCUGCCUAUCAGAAUUUCCCAAAUAUUUAGCAUCUUCCUUGAUAAUAUGUAUUUUCUUCUUGAAUUUCACUGGCCUAAUGAGAUAAUACUCUUAUCUUUGGCUCUACCUAAAAGUUGGUUAAAAAUGCAAUUGGCAUUAACAAGGAAAAAUACUGAAUUAGUAAUUUUAAAAGUCUCACAAAGAAAAUCCCAGGCCUAGAUGGCUGCAUUGUUGAAUUCUGCCAAACAUUAAAAUUAGCACUAAUUUUUUGCACACUGUUUCUAAAAGUAGGAGAGGAAAGAACACUUCCCAACUUACUCUAGGUCAGUAUUACCCUGAUACUAGACUAGACAUCACAAGAAAACUAUAAGCCAAUAUUCCUUAUUAAUACAAACACAAAAAUCAUUAACAAAAAUAUUAGCAAACUGAAUCCAGCAACCUAUAAAAAGGAUUCUAUAUCAUGACCAAGUGGAAUUUAUCCCAGGAAUUCAAGGUUGGUUCAACAUCUAAAAAUCAAAUAAGCUAAUAUACAGUCAGUUCUCAUUAUUCACAGUAAUUAUGUUCUACAGAAUAUUCUCCCAUAAACACUGAAUUAAAUAUGGAACAACUGCUUUUAGGAGAAAGUGUAUUUGUGUAUAUGUGUGUAUACAUAUGUUUAUCUCACACACAUUAUGAGCUUGAAUUCUUAAUUCAUCCUAGCAAAUUCUACCUUAUUUUACAGAAGUGAAAGUGAGGUAUCAGAAGUGUUAAGUGACAUGCCUGAGGCACCCCCCUAACAGGUGUCAGAGCUGAAAUUCAAACCCCAUCCAGCUGGCCCCGGAGCCAGAGCUUCUUGUACUACACAGAAUUGCCCCUGCCAUUUCCACCCUCCAGUCAUUUCUCUAUGAGACUGAAGCAGGAAGGCAGAGCAUCAUCUUGUUCAGCCUCAGCUGGGAACAUGUGUACUGGGUGACUCAAAUUUUUCACCCAUUUACACAUAUCCACAAAUGACUGCAAAAGUGCCACGGAUAUCAAUUUGAGGGUUAUAAAUUUUAGCAAGUUGGUAAAUUCACAAAUACAUAACCUUGAAUAAUGAGGAUCAACUGUACCAUAUUUAAUAAAGCACAAAACCCACACAGAUUGUCUUAUUACAGCAUUUGAUAAAAUCCAAAACUCUUUCAUAAAAACACUCAACAAACUUAGGAAUAAAAGGAAUCUUCCUAGAUAUGAUAAAUAUAACAUCUAUGAAAAGCCCACACCUAACAUUAUACUUCAUGGUGAUAGACUGAAGGCUGAAUGUUUUCCCCUUAAGAUUGGGAAGAAGGACAAGGAUGUUCACUCGGCACUACUUCUAUUCAGCAUUGUACUUGAAGUUCUAGCCACAGCAGUUAGGUUAGGAAUUCAAGGUUUGUUCAACAUCUAAAAAUCAAAUAAGCUAAUAAAGAAAAGAGGUUUAUACUGCAAAAGAAGUGAAACUAUAUGUAUUCACAGUUGAUACAUAGUUGUAUAUAGAAAAUGCUAAAGAAUCCAUAAAAAGUAAUAAAUGAGUUCAACAGGUUGCAGGAUACAAGAUCAGUUUUAUUUCUCUACUAACAGCAAACAUUCUGAAAAUGAGAAUAAAGAAAUCCUAUAUACAGUAGCAUCAAGAAUAAAACUCCAACACGUUUAAAGAAAUUAAGAUCCAGAUAAAUGGAAAGACAUCCAUGUUCAUGGAUUGGAAGACUGAAUAUUGGUAAGAUGGCAAUGCUGCCCAAAUUAGUCUACAUAUUCAACAAUUCCUAUCAAAAUCCUAGCUGUAUUUUUUGCAGAAAUUGACAAACUGGUAAAAUUGGUAGGGAAACGCAGGGGACCCAGAAUAGCCAAAAAACCUUGGAAAAGAACAAAGUUGGAAGACGUACCAAUUUCAAAAAGUGCUACCAAGCUACAAUAAGACAGUGUAGGCAUAUGGAUAGACAUAUCGAUCAGAGGAAUGGAACUGAACAUCCAGAAAUAAACCCAUACAUUUCUGGUCAACUUGUUUUCAACAAGGAUGCCAAUACCAUCAAUAGAGAAGGAGUGGUCUUUUCAACAAACGGUGCUGGGACAACUAACUGGUAGCUACGUGCACAGCAAAAGGAUCCCUACCUUCCUACCACAUUACAAAUUCUAACUCAAAAUGGAUCAUAGACCUCAAUAUAAGAGUUUAAACUCUUAGAAGAAAACAGAAGUAAAUCUUUGUGAUGUUGGGCUUAGGAAUGGUUUCUUAGACAUAAUACCAAAAGCACAAGCAACAAAGGCAAACAGUAGAUAAAUGGGACUUCAUCAAAAUUAACUUUAGCGCCUUAAAGGACACCAUUAAGAAAGUGAAGUUAACCCUCAGAAUGGGAGAAAAAUUUUUGAAAAAUCAUGUAUCUGAUAAAAAAACAAACAAACAUGCAGGUGCUCAGCUGUGGUUACCACCGAGCAGCACUGUCCAGUGAACUUGCUGUGAUGAUGGGAUGCUUGGUAUCCGCACUCCCAGUGUGAUAGCCUUUAGCCUCAUGGGGUUGUUGAGCAGUUGAAAUAAUAGCUAGUGUGAGGAACUGAACAUAAAAUUUUAGUUUUAGGAUGGGUGUGGUGGCUCACGCCUAUAAUCUCAGCACUUUGGGAGGCCAAUGAAGGCGGAUCACUUGAGCCCAGGAGUUCAAGACCAGCUUGACCAAGAUGGCAAAACCCUGUCUCUAUUAAAAAUACAAAAAAAUUAGCUGGGCAUGGUGGCACACACCUGUAAUCCCAGCUACUAGGGAGGCUGAGGCAGGAGAAUCGUACUUCCCCUUUAUACUCUUCUGUAUAUUUGAUUUUUUUUUUUUUAAGACAGAGUCCUGGCUCUGUCGCCCAGGCUGGAGUGCAGCGACAUAGUCUCAGCUCACUGCAGCAUCCGUGGAGGCUGAAACAGGAGAAUCGCAUGAAUUUUUUAAAAAAUCUAAACAUGUAAUUUUAAAACGGGCUUAAGAAGAAUGAUAACAGUUUUGGUCUUCUUUUUUAUCAACCAUGCUUUUAUUUUACUUGAAUCUCGUGCCAAUUGCUUUGUAAUAUUAAAGUAGGAUUUACACAAGUGGAAUUUAGAAAAGAUGAUAAUCUAUCAAAUCUGUCAAUACCAAUUAGAAUGUAAUAAAGAAAUUAGGAUAGUGGAGGUUUGAGCAAGUAAAGGCUCACCCAAAUUCAAAGCCAAUACUUGAUGCUGAGAGGGGAUAUUUUCUGGAAGGUAAUUUUUAAAAAUUAAAGUCACAAUUAUAAAUUGUAUAUUUCCUAAUAAAAGAAAUCUCAACUCAUGGGACAAUUUGAAUUUAAAACACUAUUGUUCCUCAUUCAGUGAUGAACAAGUCAAAACGUUUCAGAAAAGAAAGCCUUUAAAGAAGAAUCCUGGCACAGAAAAGGUCCAUUUAGACAUUGCCUUCUUCCCCCAUCUCUAAUGCCUCUUUUCAAAUCUCUGACUUGCACAUGAAGUAACAGUGAGGUGUCCUGUGCAGCAGUCGCAAUUUUUUGACUUGUCAAAUUGAAGAAAUUCAAUUAUGUAGCCAGAGCUUAGAUCACUGACAUGUAUACUGGCAUAAGCUUUUUUUUGUUUGUUUUUAAUUUUAUUAGAAGUGGGAUCUCAUUUUGUUGCCCAUGCUGGUCUCAAACACCUGUCUUCAAGUGAUCCUCCUGCCUCAGCAGCAUCAGUUUAAUAUCUAGAUAAAAUCUGAUGUAUGUAAUUUUACUUUUAAGGGUUUUUUUCCAAACAGACGUCCUGACAAUGUUGUUUCCUAUUCCUUGAACAUUCACCUGACGCUUAUAUACUGUCAUUACUUUUAUCUGUCAACUGAUGUCAGCUACUCAAUUUACACAUUACUUUUGUGCAUUUCAUCCUGUUUCUCAGUUUGACAUUGUCAUUCAAAUUCAGAGUUUGACACUGAAACCCUGGGCAUGGUGGCUCACACCUGUAAUCCCAGCACUUCGGGAGACUGCGGUAAGCAGAUCAUUUGAACCCAGGAGUUUGAGACUAGCCUUGGCAACAUGGUGAAACCCCAUCUCUACCAAAAAAAAAAAAAAAAAAAAAGCAAAAACAAAAAUUAACUGGGCAUAGUUGCACACACCUGUAGUCCCAGCUACUCAGGAGGCUGAAGUGGGACGAUCGCUUGAGCCCAGAAGGCAGAGGUUACGGUGAGUAGAGAUUGUGCCACUGCACUCCAGCCUGGACGACAGGGCAAGACGCUGUCUCAAAAAUAAAAUAUUAGUAAAGAAGAGUACAAUCAGAAUAUGAAAAUGUGUAAAUGUGCAUAUUCUCUUUUUUUCUAAUUUGGUAGCAUUAAAAAUACUUAAGCAUCAAAGUUUGGCUUUAUGAAGAAGGAGUCUGAGACACCUCAGGUUUCAGCCCUUACUAAUAGCGUGGCUCAAAGAGCGUUAACUUGCCUGUGCUUCUGUUUCCUUAUCUGUAAAAUGGGGAUGAUGCUGUAACAUCAAAGAGCUUAUAAUACUUUCCAGAGCUGGCAGUACUAAAUAAGACCAUUCCUCUAAAGUGCCAGCAUUUUGAAAAGCAUCAACCCAUCAACCUUGUGCUUUAAAUCUGGCAUUCUUAAAGCUAUACCUGUAGGCAGUAUAGAGUGUUUUUUUUUAUUUGUUUUUUUGUUGUUGUCUUUUGAGUCUCACUCUGUCUCCCAGGCUGUAGUGCAGUGGCACGUCUUGGUUCGCCGCAACCUCCGCCUCCCAGGUUCAAGCGAUUCUCGUGCCUCAGCCCCCCGCAUAGCUGGCAUUACAGGCACACACCACCACGCCCAGCUAAUUUUUGUAGUUUUAGUAGUAUCUACUAAAAUAAACAGGGUUUCACCAUGUUGGCCAGGCUGGUCUCAAACUCCUGACCUCAAGUGAUCUGCCUGCCUCGGCCUCCCAAAGUGCUGGGAUUACAGGCGUGAGUCACCAUGCCCGGCCGGCAGUGUAUAUCUUCUAAAGUUGCAAUUUUUGUUCACUCCAGAAUCACUUUUCAAAAAGCAUGCAGAUUUAAUGCCACCAGUUUGUGUUAUGUAUCUAUCCCGCAAAACAGCUCUAAAGGUGAUUUACUAAAAGAUUAACAGCAUUUAUCUCUGGUGGGAUAAUUUUUCUUUGCUUGUUUACCUGUGUCUUGCAGAUUUUACACAGUGAACAAUGACUGUAUAAUUUUAAAAUACAGAUAUGCACAAUUGUGUAAUGUAAAUAUGCUCAGCUUCAAUACAUUUAAGAACACAUUUUUAACUUUUCGUAAGGAGUCUUCAGUUUAAAAGUACAGUGUCAUUACAGAGUGCUUAUUCUGUUACAAAAUUAGUAAAGCUGAUUCUGCCUCUAAAUCUGAAGUAAUUCCCACUUUUUUUCAUGCUUGAGUUUAGUUGAUAAAUAGCAUUUUAGAUACUAAAAAUGAUUGGAUGAGUAUUUCUACAUUAAUAAGUUGCUAAUUAGGCACCAGGGUAGCAGAUAGAAUGCCUUUCUGUGUGCUAGGUUUAAACAUUUUACACACAGUCUUAUUUAAAACAGCCUUGCAGUUUAUAGAUGAACUGAUUGUUAGGCUAACCAGAGGUGUUACUAUACCCUCCAGGAUAACCCAGCUAGUAAGGGCAGAGCCAGGAUGAUUCAGACCCAGACCAGAGCCGGGUGUUUUGUCCACAGUACUGCUGCUGCUUAUACCGUAACGGGAAAAGUACACAACAGUGUCUUAAUAUUUCAUUCUUCCAUGAAAAACACUUUUAAAAUAUUGAAACAUUAUAGGAGCAGAAGUACAUCUCUAAAUAUACUUUUAGGUCACAUUGAAAACAUUUCCAAAGGAUUUGACCUGAAGUUAAUGUUGCUACAUUAUGCUCAAUACAGCAGGCUGUUCUGCUAGGGAAAUUGUUAAUAUUUUAAAAAUAUUUUCCUAAGCUUUAGCUUUACCA